AGAAGACUGGACUCAAUUCUGAAGGUCGCCAAGAAGGAGAGAACAAUGUCUUCUUUACCCGUGAGUUGAAAAGGCACAGCCUUCAAAAAUUUCGUGUCACACAAACCAAGAAAGAAAUGGGAGAUUUUAUGAGAUGAAAAUAUGAGCAUUUUUGCUGUGAAUGCUUUACUUAGAGCUAUUGAGGUGUGGAAUAGAAACCCUGAGGCUAUGGUAUCUGAGAUGCUUGUGGGGAUUGCGGUGUGGACCCUGGACCAGUGUAACCUUCGGUGAGUGUGAGGUGGUGUCUGAUGAGCAUAAACUCUGCGGAGAUAAUGUGACUUUAAGUGGGAGGUGGAUUACCCACCAGGACGAGCAGGUGUGUGAAUGGAGAGUAAAGGGGUGAGUCGGCUUUGUUUCCUGUCUAUGAUGUGAGUAUGUGUGUGAGCACAGCCAGACCAGUGCAUGAGCAUCGUUAUGUGCACAGUGAGCAGGUGUGUGUGACGCAGUGAGUGGUGUGGCUCUGUGUGACUGUGAGUGUGUGUGCUGGGAUGUGACUGUAUGUUGAAGUGGGAUCAUGCAUGUGGCUUUCUUCACAUGUGAAUGUUUCUCCCCACACAGCAGCACCUCUGAUGUGAAUCCCAUGUGGCUUAACUGGUGGGGAUCUUGGGGAUUGUGAGUUACCAAGGACUUAUUUCAGAUCACUUGUGAGAGCAGAAUGUAUGAUCAGUAGAUGUCUCUUCCCAGUAAGAGUGGGGAAGAGGAAUGCAGACUAUGGGGGUGAUGGUUCCUCAGGUGGGGUCUGCACAGAGUGACCACUGUCUCUUGCCUCCCAGGCUCAGCUUGCCUGUCCCUAGCCCAUCCAGUUCUUCCCACUGUGUGACAGGAGGGUGUGCAGAUACUGGUUUGUUAGGGAAGGACAUUAGAGGCCGUGAUUUCAGAGACUGAAUCACACAAAAUAUCCACUGUAAGCUCUGUCUGAACUGAGACUAAACUUGUUCUACACCCAUGAAAGAACAAGUUAAGUCUCAGUUCAGAAGGAGCUUACAGUGGAUAUUAAUCAACCAAGCAGCUGGGUUCACUGGCUUAUGGCUAUAAUCCCACCAAUUUUGGAGGCAAAGAUGAGAGGAUAACGAGGCCAGAAGUUUGAGACCAGUCUGGGUAUCAGAGUGAGACCCUUUCUUUAAAAAACUUUAAAUAUUUGACUGGCAGAGAGGCAGGUACCUUUCUUCCCAGCUAUUCAAGAGGGAGCAGAUGUGUGAGAUUCACUGCAGCCCAGGAGUCUGAGGUUUCAGUGAACCAUGAUUGCAUCCCUGCAUGUCAGCCUGGGUGACAGAGCAAGAACCUAUCUCAAAAGUACAGAAAAAUCAUCUCAUCUACUUGUAGUCAUCAUAGAAAUCAAUCAUUCCCUCCAGUUAUGUCCCUGACCCACAAGCUUCAUUUGUGCAAGUACUGGGGCUGUGCUCUCAGUAGUGUGUGCCCCUUCUUGGAAGGAUGUCCAUGGCCCUUGAUGAUAGUGAUGCAUGUGCCAUACAAACUGCCUGUGUCUUUGUCUGUUGGUUCCUGCGUGAUAAUCAAAGGGACACCAAUCCACUCUUUUAUCAAUGACCCACAGCUGCAGGUGGAUUUCUACACUGACAUGGAUGAGGAUUCAGAUAUUGCCUUCCGUUUCCGAGUGCACUUUGGCAAUCAUGUGGUCAUGAACAGGCGUGAGUUUGGGAUAUGGAUGUUGGAGGAGACAACAGACUACGUGCCCUUUGAGGAUGGCAAACAAUUUGAGCUGUGCAUCUACGUACAUUACAAUGAGUAUGAGAUAAAGGUCAAUGGCAUACGCAUUUACGGCUUUGUCCAUCGAAUCCCGCCAUCAUUUGUGAAGAUGGUGCAAGUGUCGAGAGAUAUCUCCCUGACCUCAGUGUGUGUCUGCAAUUGAGGGAGAUGAUCACACUCCUCAUUGUUGAGGAAUCCCUCUUUCUACCUGACCAUGGGAUUCCCAGAACCUGCUAACAGAAUAAUCCCUGCUCACAUUUUCCCCUACACUUUGUCAUUAAAACAGCACGAAAACUCA